AUGGAUGGAGAGAAUCACUCAGUGGUAUCUGAGUUUUUGUUUCUGGGACUCACUCAUUCAUGGGAGAUCCAGCUCCUCCUCCUAGUGUUUUCCUCUGUGCUCUAUGUGGCAAGCAUUACUGGAAACAUCCUCAUUGUGUUUUCUGUGACCACUGACCCUCACUUACACUCCCCCAUGUACUUUCUACUGGCCAGUCUCUCCUUCAUUGACUUAGGAGCCUGCUCUGUCACUUCUCCCAAGAUGAUUUAUGACCUGUUCAGAAAGCGCAAAGUCAUCUCCUUUGGAGGCUGCAUCGCUCAAAUCUUCUUCAUCCACGUCGUUGGUGGUGUGGAGAUGGUGCUGCUCAUAGCCAUGGCCUUUGACAGAUAUGUGGCCCUAUGUAAGCCCCUCCACUAUCUGACCAUUAUGAGCCCAAGAAUGUGCCUUUCAUUUCUGGCUGUUGCCUGGACCCUUGGUGUCAGUCACUCCCUGUUCCAACUGGCAUUUCUUGUUAAUUUAGCCUUCUGUGGCCCUAAUGUGUUGGACAGCUUCUACUGUGACCUUCCUCGGCUUCUCAGACUAGCCUGUACCGACACCUACAGAUUGCAGUUCAUGGUCACUGUUAACAGUGGGUUUAUCUGUGUGGGUACUUUCUUCAUACUUCUAAUCUCCUACGUCUUCAUCCUGUUUACUGUUUGGAAACAUUCCUCAGGUGGUUCAUCCAAGGCCCUUUCCACUCUUUCAGCUCACAGCACAGUGGUCCUUUUGUUCUUUGGUCCACCCAUGUUUGUGUAUACACGGCCACACCCUAAUUCACAGAUGGACAAGUUUCUGGCUAUUUUUGAUGCAGUUCUCACUCCUUUUCUGAAUCCAGUUGUCUAUACAUUCAGGAAUAAGGAGAUGAAGGCAGCAAUAAAGAGAGUAUGCAAACAGCUAGUGAUUUACAAGAGGAUCUCAUAA